ACUUCCGCCCAGGUGAGGCAGGGCCGACACCGAGCCCGCCCGACCCGGGCUCCCACCUGCUCCUCCAGCGCACCAGGUGUCUUUAAGAGUGAUUGAAGAGAAUAAUUCAAAAUGCCUGAAAAUCCUGCUACAGAUAAACUGCAGGUGCUGCAGGUACUUGAUCGCCUGAAAAUGAAAUUGCAGGAGAAGGGUGACACGUCGCAGAAUGAGAAGUUAUCUAUGUUUUAUGAGACACUAAAGAGUCCUCUCUUCAACCAGAUACUCACACUUCAGCAGUCCAUCAAGCAACUGAAGGGUCAACUCAACCAUAUACCCUCAGAUUGUUCAGCCAACUUUGAUUUUUCUAGGAAAGGUUUGUUAGUGUUCACAGAUGGUUCCAUCACUAAUGGAAAUGUCCACAGGCCCUCUAAUAACUCGACUGUAUCUGGGUUAUUUCCGUGGACCCCGAAGUUGGGAAAUGAAGACUUUAACUCAGUCAUUCAACAGAUGGCUCAGGGCCGGCAAAUUGAAUAUAUAGAUAUAGAACGGCCUUCAACUGGAGGCCUUGGAUUCAGUGUGGUGGCCCUCAGAAGUCAAAAUCUCGGAAAAGUUGAUAUCUUCGUGAAGGAUGUCCAGCCAGGGAGUGUAGCAGACAGGGAUCAAAGAUUAAAGGAAAAUGAUCAAAUAUUGGCCAUUAAUCACACGCCAUUGGAUCAGAACAUUUCCCAUCAGCAAGCAAUUGCAUUAUUACAACAAACCACUGGAUCUUUGAGACUGAUUGUGGCCAGGGAACCAGUCCACACAAAAAGCAGUACUUCUAGCAGCCUAAAUGAUACAACUCUGCCUGAAACAGUUUGUUGGGGCCAUGUUGAAGAGGUUGAGCUCAUUAAUGAUGGCUCUGGACUAGGUUUUGGAAUAGUUGGAGGAAAAACAAGUGGCGUGGUUGUGAGGACUAUAGUUCCUGGAGGAUUAGCAGAUCGAGAUGGAAGACUCCAGACAGGGGACCACAUCUUGAAGAUUGGUGGCACAAACGUGCAGGGAAUGACCAGUGAGCAAGUUGCACAAGUUCUAAGGAACUGUGGGAAUUCAGUCAGGAUGCUCGUUGCUAGAGAUCCAGCUGGUGACAUUUCAGUCACCCCCCCUGCCCCUGCAGCCUUACCUGUUGCCCUGCCUACUGUAGCCAGCAAGGGCCCUGGUUCUGACAGUUCUCUUUUUGAAACUUAUAAUGUUGAGCUUGUGAGAAAAGAUGGGCAGAGUCUUGGAAUUAGAAUUGUUGGCUAUGUUGGAACAUCUCAUACAGGGGAAGCUUCAGGGAUUUAUGUGAAAAGUAUAAUACCUGGCAGUGCUGCGUACCACAAUGGCCACAUUCAAGUGAAUGACAAAAUAGUUGCUGUCGAUGGCGUGAACAUUCAGGGUUUUGCCAACCAUGAUGUUGUUGAAGUAUUACGAAAUGCAGGGCAGGUGGUACACCUAACCCUAGUUCGAAGGAAGACAUCCUCAUCUACUUCUCCACUUGAACCACCUUCAGACAGAGGAACUGUUGUAGAACCACUGAAACCACCAGCUCUCUUUCUAACUGGAGCAGUGGAAACUGAAACUAAUGUGGAUGGUGAAGAUGAGGAAAUUAAAGAAAGAAUUGAUACUUUAAAAAAUGACAACAUACAAGCCUUAGAAAAAUUGGAAAAAGUCCCAGACUCUCCAGAAAAUGAGCUGAAAUCCAGAUGGGAAAACCUGUUGGGUCCUGAUUAUGAAGUAAUGGUUGCUACUUUGGACACACAGAUUGCAGAUGAUGCUGAGUUACAGAAAUAUUCAAAGCUGCUGCCUAUUCACACUCUGAGGCUUGGUGUGGAAGUGGAUUCCUUUGAUGGGCACCAUUAUAUUUCUUCAAUUGUUUCUGGUGGUCCUGUUGAUACAUUGGGUCUCCUACAGCCAGAAGAUGAGCUGCUUGAGGUCAAUGGCAUGCAGCUUUAUGGAAAAUCUCGCCGAGAAGCAGUCUCCUUUCUUAAAGAAGUGCCACCCCCUUUUACUUUGGUUUGCUGUCGGAGGUUGUUUGAUGAUGAAGCUUCUGUAGAUGAACCAAGGCGCACUGAAACCUCUCUUCCUGAGACAGAGGUUGACCACAAUAUGGAUGUCAAUACUGAAGAAGAUGAUGAUGGGGAAUUAGCACUGUGGUCCCCUGAAGUCAAGAUUGUUGAACUAGUAAAAGAUUGUAAAGGUUUGGGAUUCAGCAUUUUGGAUUACCAGGACCCUUUAGAUCCUACAAGAUCAGUGAUUGUGAUCCGCUCCCUGGUAGCAGAUGGUGUAGCAGAAAGAAGUGGGGGACUAUUACCUGGAGACCGCCUGGUCUCAGUCAAUGAAUACUGUUUGGACAACACCUCACUUGCUGAAGCUGUGGAAAUAUUGAAAGCUGUGCCACCAGGCCUAGUACACCUUGGCAUCUGUAAGCCUUUGGUGGAAGAUAAUGAAGAAGAAAGUUGUUAUAUUUUACAUUCAAGCAGUAAUGAAGACAAGACUGAAUUUUCAGGAACAAUUCAUGAUAUAAAUUCAUCUUUAAUACUCGAAGCACCCAAGGGAUUUAGAGAUGAACCAUAUUUUAAAGAAGAACUUGUGGAUGAACCAUUUCUAGAUCUGGGAAAGUCUUUCCAUUCCCAACAAAAAGAGAUAGAGCAAAGCAAGGAGGCCUGGGAGAUGCAUGAAUUUCUGACUCCUAGAUUGCAGGAAAUGGAUGAAGAAAGAGAAAUUCUUGUUGAUGAAGAAUAUGAGUUAUAUCAAGAUCCCUCACCAUCCAUGGAGUUGUAUCCCUUGUCGCACAUUCAAGAGGCCACUCCUGUGCCCUCUGUGAAUGAACUUCACUUUGGUACACAGUGGUUGCAUGAUAAUGAACCAUCCGAGUCUCAAGAGGCAAGAACCGGGAGGACUGUCUAUUCCCAGGAGGCACAGCCGUAUGGCUAUUGCCCUGAAAAUGUGAUGAAAGAAAAUUUUGUCAUGGAGUCCCUACCAUCUGUACCAUCAACUGAAGGAAACAGUCAACAAGGCAGAUUUGACGACCUGGAAAAUCUUAAUUCAUUAGCAAAAACUAGUCUGGAUUUAGGCAUGAUCCCGAAUGAUGUCCAAGGUCCUAGCUUGCUCAUUGACCUUCCUGUUGUGGCUCAAAGGAGGGAGCAAGAAGAUUUGCCUUUAUAUCAACACCAAGCGACACGAGUUAUUUCCAAGGCCUCAGCAUACACAGGAAUGUUGUCUUCUAGAUAUGCCACUGAUACAUGUGAGUUACCUGAGAGAGAAGAAGGCGAAGGAGAAGAAACUCCAAAUUUUAGCCACUGGGGUCCACCGAGAAUUGUUGAGAUUUUUAGAGAACCCAAUGUGUCUCUUGGGAUCAGUAUUGUUGGUGGACAAACUGUUAUAAAACGUCUAAAGAAUGGAGAGGAGCUUAAAGGUAUAUUCAUCAAACAAGUUUUAGAAGACAGUCCAGCAGGGAAGACGAACGCACUUAAAACUGGAGAUAAAAUACUUGAGGUGUCUGGAGUAGAUUUGCAGAAUGCCUCACACAGCGAAGCAGUUGAGGCCAUUAAGAAUGCAGGAAACCCUGUGGUGUUCAUUGUUCAGAGUUUGUCAUCCACUCCACGAGUCAUUCCUAACGUACAUAACAAGGCCAACAAAAUCACCGGUAACCAGAACCAGGACACCCAAGAAAAGAAAGAAAAGAGGCAAGGAACUGCUCCACCGCCAAUGAAACUUCCUCCUCCUUAUAAAGCUCUGACUGAUGACAGUGAUGAAAAUGAAGAAGAAGAUGCCUUUACCGACCAAAAAAUCAGACAAAGAUAUGCAGAUCUGCCUGGAGAACUGCACAUUAUUGAACUUGAAAAAGAUAAGAAUGGACUUGGACUCAGCCUUGCUGGUAAUAAAGACCGAUCACGCAUGAGCAUAUUUGUGGUGGGAAUUAACCCGGAAGGACCUGCUGCCGCAGAUGGACGAAUGCGUAUUGGAGAUGAACUCUUAGAGAUAAACAAUCAGAUUCUGUAUGGAAGAAGUCACCAAAAUGCAUCUGCCAUUAUUAAGACUGCCCCAUCAAAGGUCAAGCUGGUUUUCAUCAGAAACGAGGAUGCAGUCAAUCAGAUGGCCGUUACUCCCUUUCCAGUGCCAUCAAGUUCUCCAUCUUCUAUUGAGGAUCAGAGCGGCACCGAACCUAUUAGUAGUGAGGAAGAUGGCAGCGUCGAAGUUGGUAUUAAACAAUUGCCUGAAAGUGAAAGCUUCAAACUGGAAGACAUGUCCCAGGUGAUUGGUCAGGGCAUGGUGGCAGAUCAGCAGAAGGCACUGGAAUACCCACCUGACAAUGCUGUCAGCCAGAUGAAACAGCAAAAAUAUCCAACAAAAGUCUCCUUCAGUUCACAAGAGAUACCAUUAGCACCAGCUUCAUCAUACCAUUCAACAGAUGCAGACUUCACAGGCUAUGGUGGUUUCCAGGCUCCUCUGUCAGUGGACCCCGCAACGUGUCCCAUUGUCCCUGGACAGGAAAUGAUUAUAGAAAUAUCCAAGGGACGUUCAGGGCUUGGUCUCAGCAUUGUGGGAGGAAAAGACACACCCUUGUUCUGGAGGCUGGGAAGUCCAAGAGCAUGGAGCCAGCAUCUGGUGAGGGCCUUCAUGCUGCAUCAUCCUGUGACAGAAGUUGAAGGGCAAAAUGCUAUAGUUAUCCAUGAAGUCUAUGAAGAAGGGGCAGCAGCCAGAGAUGGAAGACUUUGGGCUGGUGACCAGAUAUUAGAGGUUAAUGGGGUUGACCUGAGGAACUCCAGCCACGAAGAAGCCAUCACAGCCCUGAGGCAGACCCCCCAGAAGGUGCGGCUGGUGGUGUAUAGAGAUGAGGCACACUACCGGGAUGAGGAGAACUUGGAGAUUUUCCCUGUGGAUCUGCAGAAGAAAGCUGGCCGGGGCCUGGGCCUGAGCAUCGUUGGGAAACGAAAUGGAAGCGGAGUGUUUAUUUCUGACAUCGUGAAAGGCGGAGCCGCAGACCUGGAUGGGAGAUUGAUUCAGGGAGAUCAGAUCUUAUCUGUGAAUGGGGAGGACAUGAGAAAUGCCUCACAGGAGACAGUGGCCACCAUCCUCAAGUGUGCACAGGGACUUGUGCAGCUAGAGAUUGGAAGACUCCGAGCUGGUUCCUGGACCUCCGCAAGGACGACAUCACAGAACAGUCAGGGUAGUCAGCAGAGUGCACACAGCAGCUGUCAUCCCUCCUUCGCUCCUGUCAUCACUGGCCUGCAAAACCUGGUUGGCACAAAAAGAGUUUCAGAUCCUUCCCAGAAAAAUUCAGGCACAGAUAUGGAACCAAGGACUGUUGAGAUAAACAGGGAGCUCAGUGAUGCCCUUGGAAUCAGUAUUGCUGGAGGAAGAGGAAGUCCCUUAGGAGAUAUCCCCGUAUUUAUUGCCAUGAUUCAGGCUAGCGGAGUGGCCGCACGGACACAGAAGCUUAAAGUUGGAGAUCGGAUUGUCAGCAUUAACGGGCAACCUUUGGAUGGGCUGUCUCACGCGGAUGUGGUUAAUCUGCUGAAGAACGCCUACGGGCGCAUUAUCCUGCAGGUUGUAGCAGAUACCAAUAUAAGCGCCAUAGCAGCUCAGCUUGAAAACAUGUCUACAGGCUACCACCUUGGUUCGCCCACUGCUGAACACCAUCCAGAAGACACAGAAACACCUCCACCUAAGAUUAUUACUUUGGAGAAAGGCUCUGAAGGCUUGGGGUUUAGUAUUGUAGGGGGUUAUGGAAGUCCCCAUGGAGACCUGCCAAUUUAUGUCAAGACUGUAUUUGCAAAGGGAGCAGCUGCAGAUGACGGCCGAUUAAAACGAGGGGAUCAGAUUUUAGCUGUUAAUGGCGAGACCCUGGAAGGUGUUACUCAUGAGCAAGCAGUCGCCAUUCUAAAACACCAGAGAGGGACUGUAACCUUAACUGUGCUGUCAUGAGCCUCGGGCCUGAUCACAAGAUAGAUGUUGUUGUUUAGAAUAUCCACAGGCAGAUGAAGUUCUGAGUGGGUAUGAAAAGCACCCUCAACUAAAAUGCACCUUCAUUCUUAUUUCUUGCCCUCUCUGCUCAGGAGAAAUGGCUGAGGUUUCAUGUGAAUUUCCCAAAUCAACAAUCAUCUCCUAAUGUUUCCCAGUUCCUGUCACCUGUUGGCGAGGUUGAUUUCUAAAACUUAAAUGAGUCUACCUGUUUUGCAUUUAAUUUCAGUGUUCCGAUUUCUUUUUUUUUUUUUUUUUUUUUUUUUGAGACGGAGUCUCACUCUGUCACCCAGGCUGGAGUGCAAUGGCGCAAUCUUGGCUCACUGCAACCUCGGCCUCCCAGGUUGGAGCGAUUCUCCUGCCUCAGCCUCCCGAGUAGCUGGGAUUACAGGCAUGCAUCACCACACUGGGUUUAUUUUUGUUUUUUUAGUAGAGAUGGAGCUUCCCCAUGUGGGCCAGGCUGGUCUUGAACUUCUGACCUCAGGUGAUCUGCCUGCCUUGGCCUCCCAAAGUGCUGGGAUUCCAGGCGUGAGCCACUGCGCCCAGCCCAGUAUUCUGAUUUUAACCAACUGGUUCUGAUUAUAUUUACCAAAACUGGAGUUAACUUCUCUUUCCUUAUACUCUUCUCUCCCUAUCCCCUACUCACACCGAGGCUUAACAGCAACCUCAGAUCUCAUCCAAUGGACAGAAACAAAUGUUAAGCAACUUGUCAUCUCACUCAUGAUUUACUUAUGCUAAUUGUCUCUUCAAGUAAGCAAGAAAACAUUAGCAGUGUAAUUAAUUUACCAGUGAUCCCCAAGAUGAAAUACCAGAUUCUCCUAUGGGAAAUUACUGUGCUGUCUUCUGUAUGACUUAUGGUCAAAUAAGUCUCAAAUUCAUUUCUCUGGAUAGAUCUUUAUAUGCUAGUCAUUGGUGAUUUUGAUGAGUCAAUUUACAGACUGUAAUCUUCUAAAAAUUCUGAAAGACUAAUUGUUUUCUGUGCCAUAUAAAUGCAUACCACUGAGCAAAUGAACCUUAUUCUCAGCAGGAACAACUAGCAUACAUGUUCUGAAUUCUAACAGUGCUAAAUUACAUUCAAGUCCAGGAAGAUCACCUGGAAUUAAUGGCAUUUCAGUUGGCAGGCAUCAUUCCCACCCCUCGGUCUUAGGAAAAGGAGGUAGAAGCCCCAGAACCACACGGCAGAGAUCAGCAAGUUUUGUCUCAAGUCAGACAAGGUCUAGGUGGCCUUGGCCUUAUGCAAAGUGGGUGACAUAUUUGAUUAUAUUUCCCUUUACCUCCAUAGUAGUCAGGCCAGCAGCAUGGACUGCAAGAACCUAAGGGAGCAACAUACUUAGCUGCAAAGUGAGCAAAUGAAUUGAGCCUAGGAAUAUGUGAUGAAAAUGCAUGGCUGAUGUUUCCUGAUCUCCAAGGAGACUCCCAUUUGCUGAAGUUUUGCAUGCUAAGAAAUCAACUACAGCAGAAAAUACAAGAAUACCUUUAAGUUGAUUAUUGGCAAUCUUAUUCAUAUAUUAGCAAGAAAAAGGGAGAGAUGCUUACUGGUGGAUGCUAUAGAGUCCUCUGUUUUUAAAAGUACCAUGGCCGGGUGCAGUGGCUCACGCCUGUAAUCCCAGCACUUUGGGAGGCCAGGGCAGGCGAAUCAUGAGGUCAGGAGUUCGAGACCAGCCUGGCCAAUAUGGUGAAACCCUGUCUCUACUAAAAAUACAAAAAUUAGCUGGGUGCAGUGGCAGGCGCCUGUAAUCCCAGCUACUCCGGAGGUUGAAGCAGGAAAAUUGCUUGAACCUGGGAGGUGGAGGUUGCAGUGAGCCAAGUUCGUGCCACUCCACUCCAGCCUGGGUGACAGAGCAAGACUCUGUCUCGAAAAAGAAAAAAAACCAUGAAGGAUGAGUACUAGAGUCAGUAAUAGAAGUAGUUCAGCAUUAUUUAACUACAACACAAUGCUGCAAAUAUUUCACAGUAAUUAUCAAAAUUUAAUGGGCUCUAAUUUAAAAUGUUAUUUAAUAAGUAUAGAUUUUAAUUGAGAAUUAUCUUUGAGUAGAUGUAAUCACAAAGUGCAUUAACUCUUGUUGGAAUAUUUUAUGGCUAUUCCAAAGUAUAGAGUGCCUAAAUUUUGUGUUGAAAAUGUCUUUCAUGACGGUAUUAAGUUUUCUGAAAUUACACAUGGCUUUUAAAAUUUCUAAUGUAUCCAAGAUGUGCAAUGUUGUUAGGAUCUCAUUCUUCAGUGCAUGAAAAGCUACUACCCUCAGAACAUUUUGUGUUAAUUGUACCUGCAAGAACACCUCAGGCAAGCCAAGAAGAAAUGAAACCCAAAUAAAACUUGAAAAUGCACCUUAAAAAUAUAUAUACAUAUAAUAGUUUUGAAAUGGGAUUCUGCUUUAUUUUGAUGGAAUGGCCAUUAAAUACACAUUUUGAGAUAAUACAUUGUUGUGGUGUUUCUUUAUACAUUAUCCUUUUAGGUCGUGCUAGUAAAAGUAUAUUGAUGAAGGAAUUAUGAUGCUUUAUACUUCUUACUGCACUAAAUUGAUAGAACUAGUACUUGUCAUAAUCGGUUCUGUCUCCGCUCACAUGACUAAUACGUAAUUGCCUUUCCAAAAAGAUAUUUUUGCCUCAGAACUUACUGACAAGCUGAGAGGCUAUGAAGAUGGAAAUUUGUGAAAGAAGUAGUGCUCUUAUAUUUGGCCUCAUCAUUUGGGCCAUUUCAGUAUAGUAAUGAUAUCACUAAUCGGAAUUAGCAUGAGAGGGAAGUAAGCCAGGAAGAAUAAAACUGCUGAAUGUUUGUAUGUGUAAGAUAUUUCCAAAGAUUCUAAAUAAAUGUAGUUGCCUACAGA